GUAACCUAUGAUUUACUUCUGAGUAUUCAAAGAUCUGUUACUGAGCUCUAUACUUUUAAUCAAGAUAGUUAUUCAAGGUUUAACUUUUUAAACAUUUGUUUCUGAAGAAGAAUGGAAUAGGCUUUCCAAAUACAUAGUACUGAGGAUACAAUGGGUGGAGUAGAGAUGGCUCUUCAUUGUAAAAGUCAUCUUAAAUCCUGAUUGUCUCUACUUUAGUGAUUGUAUUAGAGGGCAACAACCUGAGACAAUAUUUCAGAGCAUCAUUCCAAGGACACACCAGGAGGAAAAAUGGCCAAAUCUUUCCCAGUAUUCUCACUUUUGUCCUUUAUCUUGAUACAUUUGGUGUUAUCUUCUGUUUCAGGCCCUAGACACUGGUGGCCACCACGUGGAAUUAUUAAGGUGAAAUGUCCAUAUGAGAAAGUAAACUUGAGCUGGUACAAUGGAACGGUCAACCCCUGCCCUGGCUUAUAUCAACCCAUCUGCGGCACCAAUUUUAUAACCUAUGAUAAUCCCUGCAUUCUGUGUGUUGAGAGCUUGAAAUCUCAUGGAAGAAUCAGGUUUUACCAUGAUGGAAAAUGUUAGCUGAGUGGACUUGAAUGUGGAAGAUAUCUUCUUUUUUUUUUCCUCCAUGUCUCCAAUCUCCCUCUUGCGCUUUUUACAUCUCCUUGCAUUUGUUCUUCAUGACAAAGAGCUAUCACUACUGAGCUUGUAGCAGAUUGUUCAAAGUUCCUUCCAUGGACCUCUCCCCUCACUGACUGAUUGCCUUCCAUAGUCUCCCUAAUAAAUACACUUUUAUGAAAGUC